CCACAGACAGCUGGAAAUGAUCCCUAUUGUUUUGUGGAGUUUCAUGAGCAUCGUCAUGCAGCUGCAGCAUUAGCUGCUAUGAAUGGACGGAAGAUAAUGGGAAGUCAAAGUGAAUUGGGCAACAACCCCUAGCAGUCAAAAGAAAGAUACAAGCAGUAGUACCGUUGUCAGCACACAGCGUUCACAAGGUAAUUGUAUCUUCUUAAACAUAAAAUGAAAUCUCUUGAAAGGGUAUUCACUAACCACCUGAAGUUUUUUUGUUUGAUAUUUGGGGGAGGGGGGCGGGAGGAGAUAUUAUUUCUAUUUGUCUCUCUAGCAAUACUUUUCUCCCUUCUCAGUGUUGACCAAGUAUAACUUGUCCGCUACUUUGGUGCUAGUUCAAGCUUUCUGACCCGUUUGGUAGCAGCUGAUGCCUUAGAACUACUUUCACCAACUAAGGGGCAAAAUACCCUCCUUUCUUGAGGUCACCAUUUGGGCUUCAUACCCAGAUCUUCCAAAUGCUUGAGUUGCUCCUCAAAUUUUGUUUCCCAAAGAGCAAUCCAAAAUGUUGUUUAAGGCCUGUCAAAUAUGGGUAACUUUUCUUUCCAAAUAUGCUUUGUCAAAUUGAUGUAUGUGUCCAUUUUAAAGUGUUGGUCCAACAAUUUUGCAUUUUUAAAGUGUUUCUUUUUUUGAUAAUUGUCUUUUUUAAAAACUUCAGAUAUGGGUUGGUUAUUUCUCUCCAAUGCUUUUUUAAUGGUUCUGAUAUAAAGUGAAGGGAUUACUGUUUUCAUUCUGUUGCCUUCAGUCUUAGUUCACUUGCACAUGGAUUCACAUAAACUGAAUGGUGUAAUGUCUGGGCAACCAAAACUGUUGGCUUUUGAGAAAACUGUCAAAUACUUUAACAUCAAACUGUUGCAAUGCAAGGUAUUUCUUUGAUUGUUCUUCACAAAAUAUGGUUAAACCAAGUAUAUAUCAUGUAGCUAGCUUCAGUAAAUUGUGUUAACUGAGGCAAAUCUAGUCUACAUAAUUCACAGUACCACUAUUUUAUUUUAAUUUGUAAAGCCUUAAUAUAGUGGUAAACUGAAUAAAAGUAAAUAAUUAUUAUUAGAAUGGUAACUAAGUCAUUAAAUUUUUUUGCAGAACUGAAACUUGUAUGUUAUUAGUUUAUUUUCUUAGACCAGUGUAAUAAUUGACUGUAAAUAGAAAUAUAAAUGUCACUUUACAGUUAGAUGUAUCACAGUCGUUUCAGGAGAAUUUUUCCUAUAUUGUUACCUUGAUUCAUUGUUUAAAAUUGGUAGGAUUUGUAUAGAUAUAGGAUAGUGUUUUAUUUAUACUUUAUCAUAAGCCAUAAUCAUUUUAAGAAUACUUUAUUGGAUAGAUUUUAGUACUUUUUAAAUUCUAAAGUUCUAUUUUUCUUUUCACUUCCCCUUCCUUCCCCUUAUAAGAUCAUUUCCAUGUCUUUGUUGGUGAUCUCAGCCCAGAAAUUACAACUGAAGAUAUAAAAGCUGCUUUUGCACCAUUUGGAAGAAUAUCGUAAGUAACAGAAGAUAAAUAAAAUCCUUUUAAUUAGAAACAAUUAUAUGUAGACAUAACUUGAAAAUAAUUCUGUUGUGAAUUUUGUACAUUAAUUUUAUAACUUGAAUAUAAUGUAUUACAUUGUUUAGAGAUCAUUCAAGAAGUUAACAGCAAAAGAUUGUUUUCCCAUUGAUGAAUAAACCUUUGGUUUUCAAUUAUCUUAAAAUCCUUUUUCAAUUAGCAUAGCUCUUAAGAGACAAAUUUGCCAUUGUACAUGUUUUACUUUCUUAUAUAGGUAUCAAGCUAGCUUGGUGACAAUCUUUAGUAAAAUUGUGCUGUAACUAAGGAAUUUAGAUCUGUUGGGUACUUCUAUGAUACCAUGCAUUUUGUGUUAAUAUAUUUUAACAAAAAGAAACCUUAACAAUUCAACUUAAAAAGCAGUUAUUGAAUAUUAUUUUCUAGAUAUUUACACCCUUUUAAAAAAACUGCUAACAAUAAUAGUGCCUUAAUAAUAUUUUAUGAAGCACUGCCUUGCUUGCACUUGUUAUUAGUCAUACAUUUUAGGCCCUUAUGAAUAAAUACCUUACUUGAGAUAGCAUUCAUCAUAGAAGAACUUUAAAAUUUUGAAAAGCAUGCCAUAUUAGAGUAAGAAUAACAAGUUGUUUACAGUACUUUCUGUAGAGUAAUUAGCUUAGAAAACUUCUUCAGGGUUUCUGCUUGCUCUGUUAUUUUUCCACCUAGAAGAAUAGUAAAAAGGAAGUGCUAGCUGUGGUUUGGUUUGAACAGACCAACAGCAGAGAUGAGAUGAGGAGACUGGAAAGUAAAUGCCAGUAGUAUUGGUGAAUUUUAGGAGCUUUCGUUUGAAGAGUUAUCGUUCCUUGAUUAGGGGAUGUGACCAAGGAAUUACCAACUUUAAAGGUGGUCACAGAAUUAGGGCUUAUAAAUGGACUUCUUUCAGAUGACAUUUUUCUUUGUGAGACCUGAUCAGGAAAAUAAGUACAGCUUUCAUUUCUUGAUUGUCCUUCUUAAUAAUAUCUUAGAGUUUCAAUAAUAAUUAGCUUGCUUUCGAAUAUCUGGACUUAGACAGUCUUAGCCUUUGGCCUCUCAAGGGCUCUAAAUCUCUAUGCACAAUUUUGUGUUUUCAUUUUGGUGUGGAAAAUCUUUGUAAAUUUUAUCCUAUUGUCAGAGUAGUCAUAGAACCAUAAAAGGAUAAAGAAGCCUGAUCUAGAUCUUUGCUGCUGCUUCAGAGAAUCUUUUCAGAGAGAAAUAAAUGAGUUGAAUAUUUUUCAAGACUAACAUUUUCUGAAACUUUAAGAAGAAAAAAUUUUCUAACAUUGUGAACAGAUUAAGUAGCUAUUUUAUUAAAUGCUUUGAUUUUAAUUGAGGUAGUUUUUUUGAAAACACGGGAAUUUUAGUUUGGAAUUAGGCAAAGAUUGUUUAACAGUUGGUGAGUUUAAGUUAAGUGACCUUCAGAUUUUAGCAAUUUCAUGAUUUACAAAUCGUGGGUUAUAUUUUUUUCUCUUAAAUAUAUUUCUGUGUCAUAUUUUUAGUCUGUAGAUUUUCUUAUGGUCCCAUGAUUAUUGGUGUAUACUUUUUUUUUCUUGGUAAGACCUUUAAGUUUUAUGAUUUUCAAUUGAGAUAAUGUAUAAUGUUUGAGUUUUAGGCUAUAUAAGGAAUUAGCUUUCCUGCAUUUAAAGGAAUCAUUUGGCAGUCAGUAGCAUAUUUUCCUGAUUUUUUGUUGUUGUUAAAGGAGAUAAGUUGAUAACUGUAUGUUGAAGGGUUCUCAUGAUAUUCUCUAAAAAGUGCAAAUAUCAGUGCUUGAUUUAUAGAUGUGUAAUAAACAGUGGUCUGUAAAAGCAUGUAGUAUAAAAAAUAUGGUAUUUUCCCUUAUAUACAGCCUAUAAACUCUUCCUAUUCCUUGAGUUUAGGGUAGACUAACAAAUUACAGCGUAGAAGAGAGUCAGCUACCAGAUUAAAUGCAUGCGUACCAUACAGAUAAUUUAUUAAGUAUUUUUGCAUAUUGAACAUUGACUUACAUUAAUUUUCCCUUUUCACCACCACGUCUUUGUCAUUUUGACCCUGAACACUUAAUAAAUCACUCAGAUUGAUCUAAAAUAUGCUUAUGUAUACUUUAAUAGAAAAUUACAUUGCAUGGCUUUCUGACUUGGGUUUUUGUUAUAAAAGUGCCUGUUUUGUUCAUGUGUCCUGAGAGAGCAAGCAUUGUGACAUACCUGACUAACUUAAAAGCAGAUUGCCUGUGAAGCACAAUUUGAGUCCAAUUUUUUGAGGUAUGGAGUUUUAGCUAUCAUGGCUGGGUUUUUACUCAAUCUCAAAUAAUAGGGCUCUGGUUAUUUUGCAGAGUGUCUCUGAAGAAUGGACAGAAUUGCCCUGGCUAACUACAAGCUACGGUUCACAGUGGAUAAAUGUUGGCGUGCUUUUUUACUUUCUGACUUUUUAAAAUUUUGCUUUUAUAUCUUGUAGUUCCAAUCAAUUUUAUAUGAAUGCUAUUAUAAAAUUCAGUGUAAAAUCUUUUCUUGUCUAGCUUAAAACUUGUGUGUGUCUAGUAUUUUUCUUCAAUGAUUUAACAUUUCUGAAAAUGUCAAGUUCUCAAAAUUUAGACAAAAAGGGGGGUAUAAAUUGAUCUGAAAAAAUUAAAUAGUUUAAUUAGUUUAGGGAAUAUACAACUUUUUCAUUCUUUUGGUUUCCAGUUUUCUAUUUUUUUUUAAUGAUUAGGUAGAAUAUAGUGUCAAAUAAGUUAUAAAUUGCAUGGUUAAAGAAAGCCAUUCAUCUAAUGUCCUGUGAACUUUAUAAGUGGUUAAGUAGUUCAUGUGAGUAGCUGCUUUCACCAUGCUUAAUAUUUAAAAGUUUAAAAAGUUUUUUGAAGAGAGAGGCAAUUUCUGUACAAUAUAAAUAUACAUAUAUACUUAAGUUAUUGAUUUGCAUGUCUAUAAAAUUAAGCCUCAUUUCCUAAUACAUGAUAAAUUUUGUAGAAUAAAAGGUGAAUUUGCAUUAAAGGUUCACUUUAAUGAAGGUGAAACAUGAGAAUGAGUUGUGUGUGAAAUUCUUAUUUGAUAUCCAGAGGAUAGUUUGCAAACCUAAACUUCUGAUUGUUUCUGAUUUCAGAGAUGCCCGAGUGGUAAAAGACAUGGCAACAGGAAAGUCUAAGGGAUAUGGCUUUGUCUCCUUUUUCAACAAAUGGGAUGCUGAAAACGCCAUUCAACAGAUGGGUGGCCAGUGGCUUGGUGGAAGACAAAUCAGAACUAACUGGGCAACCCGAAAGCCUCCCGCUCCAAAGAGUACAUAUGAGUCAAAUACCAAACAGCUAUCAUAUGAUGAGGUUGUAAAUCAGUCUAGUCCAAGCAACUGUACUGUAUACUGUGGAGGUGUUACUUCUGGGCUAACAGAACAACUAAUGCGUCAGACUUUUUCACCAUUUGGACAAAUAAUGGAAAUUCGAGUCUUUCCAGAUAAAGGAUAUUCAUUUGUUCGGUUCAAUUCCCAUGAAAGUGCAGCACAUGCAAUUGUUUCUGUUAAUGGUACUACCAUUGAAGGUCAUGUUGUGAAAUGCUAUUGGGGCAAAGAAACUCUUGAUAUGAUAAAUCCCGUGCAACAGAAUCAAAUUGGAUAUCCCCAACCUUAUGGCCAGUGGGGCCAGUGGUAUGGAAAUGCACAACAAAUUGGCCAGUAUAUGCCUAAUGGUUGGCAAGUUCCUGCAUAUGGAAUGUAUGGCCAGGCAUGGAACCAGCAAGGAUUUAAUCAGACACAGUCUUCUGCACCAUGGAUGGGACCAAAUUAUGGAGUGCAACCGCCUCAAGGGCAAAAUGGCAGCAUGUUGCCCAAUCAGCCUUCUGGGUAUCGAGUGGCAGGGUAUGAAACCCAGUGAAUAAGGACUCCAGAAUCUAAAGCCAGUGGCUUGAGGCUACAGGGAGUGUAGUAAAGCCGUUGUUUACUUAAAGAUUUAUCAAAUCAGUCAGUGCAAAUGUCAGAUACAAUGUAUUUAUUUAAAAGAUUCAUUUUUAAUCAUGAAAUUACUUAUCAUCCACAUUGUUUUAAAAAGAAACAAGAUGCUGGAUGUCUGCCAAUUUUUGCCUUCAUUACCUUUUUUGAUAAAGUUUCUCAGAUCCUUGUUUCAAACACAAAUGCAGGGAUUGCUGCCACUUUUUAACUAUUAAGAGGCAGAAAAUUGCACAAUAUUGAACUUUUUUCCACUGAAGUAGUGUGCAGUUCUAGUUUGCAUUCCUGAUAUGAUUUAAAACAUGUAAUAUAAAGAUGUUAAAAAAAAAAACCAAAACUGUGCAGAGUCUAGAAGUUGUUUGUCAUCUUCAGCUUGUGCACAAUUCUGUUUUAGGUUAAAAAAAGGCAUUGUUUGAGCUGUCCCAUCUCCACUGUUAUCCCUUUGGGGUUUUUUAAUAUAAAUUAUUAGUUUACAUCAUUUUUGUAUCUACAUCUUUUUUCACAAAUUUGUCUUGCCUUAUUAAAGUUCUGUAAAAUAUACUUAAAUGGAAAAAAUGAUGUUCAUUUAGAUUGAAAACUUUUCUCAGAUGGAUUGAUAAUUGCAUUCAUCUUGUGUUUUAUAUGAGAAGGUGCCUCAAGAAUUUCCUGUUGGAUUUGUUUAAAAGGAUUUUUAUCUUUCGUGAUAAACUUUGCUGUGUACCAGGAACUAUAAAAACAAAAACUUGUUACUAAAGAAAAUAUCUGAAAUGUGAUAAGUUCUUAUGCCAUGUUAAUUUCAUGUGUCAACUUCAACAUUUACAUGUAUUAUUUCAUUAUGUAAAAUGUUUUAGCAAUUUAAUAUUUUGCACAGUUAGCAAACUUUGUAUGUCAUUUCCUUCAAGGCAUCAUGCAGAGUUGACAUGAGAUUUAUAAGGUUUUAAGUUGUUUGCAUGUGAAAAUCAAAUACAUACUUUGGUAGUCUUUGAAUACAAAGUCAUCUGCUCUUGUUUUUCAAGAAUUUUGAGACACAAAGUUGUAUGUAAAGGAAUAUAUUAAUUUGCCGUUUUCUAGGUAGAUUUGCUCAAAAAGAGUGAAUCAACUUAAUAUGUACAAAUGAUAGCUGUGAAACUGUAGAAUAUCUUUGUGUCAGGCUUGGAGUUCAUUGUGACCUCCAAAUUUUGCCUGAAGGACCAGCUGGGCAAAGCAUCUUUUAAAUGUUCAGAGGCCAAAAGAUAAACAAAAAAAAAACCUUAAAAUCCUACCUCUUUAAACAGCCUUCAGAUAAGAGAAUCCUCAGUGCAAUCAUUAUUUUGAUUCGUUUGGUACCUGUUUUCCUGGAGUUCCCGAUUUUAUUAUUUUGGGGUGGCUCCAAGCAUUAAGAGGUUUAAUCUUUGAUGGCAUUGUUCUAGUUUUGAAAUUUCUAGUAUAUUUCAGAGUCUCUUAGAAGACUUGUGUGGGAAGUUUCACUUUGUUUUCAGUGAAGAUCACAAACCUCCUUCUUCCUUUACUCAAGAGGAAAGGUCCCAGUAUACAUAUUUGAAUGGUUGAUGGUUUUCAAGACCUUCAGGGAGCUCCCUGCAUUUUACCUAGAAACAGAAAAGGCCCGCAAAAUCUUAAGUUUCCUGGCCUGCAUUUCCCGGGUAGGGGCAAAUGACUCCAAGCUGGUCUCUAAGCCAAUACCCUUAUAAACCAGAGCCCAGGAAAGACAGCUCGAGUGUAUAAUUCUCUGGAGCUCAAUUCUAUGCAGUUGUGCUGAUAUUUCAUUAAGUCACUGUGUAUUUUUAAGUGUUGAUACAUUAAAAGUCGCUUUAUGGAAGAUGAGUAAAUUUUUUAAAUACUUGGAAAUUUUAUUUCCUUGUUAACUUCUACAGAUCAGGGCAUGCAACCAAAAGCAGCUUAAAUGAAAUAUUUUAAAAUAAAAUAUCAGGAAGCUAUUUUUAGAUUUCUUCUGGCUUAUGUUUCUACUUUAGGACCCUCAUUGUUCUCUUAUUAAAAAAAAUUAUUUCCUGUGCAUCUCAUGGACUGCAGGGUAAAUUAUUUGGGCAUAAAUAAUUUAAAUAGUUUUCUUUCAUUUUGACUAUCUCCAGUAAUAACAGUUUUUAUUAUCCAGCAUAUUGGCUUAUUGCACAAAUCUUAAAAUGUACAUUGACUACUUUCUGAGAAGAAAGUGGUAUCAGUACUCAUGAUGAAAAGGUUACUACUGAACAAAUUCACAUUUCAGGAACACCUCUAUCUUUGGUUUAAAUCUUACUCUUAGUUUUUCCGUCUAAAAAUCAUACUGGUAUUAGUAUCAGGUAAGGAAAUUAAAGUUUUUAAAAUGGUUUCAUUCUCUGCAAUAUGCAAAAUUUAGAUUUUACUUUCUGGUACUGUAAAGAACCUGAAGUGAUUUACACUUAAUGGGUGAUUAAUCCAGUAUUCUUUACCCUGAAUGUUUGGAUAUUAAAGUUCCUUUAUGUUUUCUAUAACCUGUGGGAUCUUCUUGCAGUGAUUAUUGUGUGUGAGAUUUUUUUUCUUUUUGGUCUAUCCAUAUUGUUAUAUUCACUCAGGUAUUUUUUUUUUAAUCUUAUUCCAGAAUCAGUGGUUUAUAUUGGGUUACUGUUUAACACCAAAUGGAAUUGGCAUUCUGCAGAUUUAAUUAAUUAUGAAACCAGGGUCUCAUUUUCCUUGCUGAUACUUGUUGAAAAUGAGAUUCACAUUCUAGUCUUUAUUUUCCUCCUGUUUUGUCCCUGUGCUUGUACAUCUUCCUUUUAUUUGUGUGUUAUAGUUCUAUUCCAUUUGAGAAGGCAGUUGGUAAGAACUAGAUUGCAUGUACAAAGACAGGUUUACUAAGUGCUGUACAGUGGUCCUGAGGUUACAGUUGAAUUAGAAAAACGAAAUGUACUUACAGGAAAUAAGAAAGCAAACCUUUCAAAUGAGAGUGAUGAUUUCUUUAAAAAAAAUCAGUUUUUUUCUCUCAAAUAAUGUUCUUUAUUUCACGAAAUCGUCAAUCUUAAGCAUGAGCAGGGAUAAACAACUCCUAGAAGGAACUCAAUUCAUUCUUCCUGGAUUUUCUCUGUUGUUAAAUCACAAAAAUGAUAGUCCCCAAUCGUUUCUUUAUAGGAGGUUAUUACAUUUCAUUACAGUCACUGCAUUUUGACUGUUGUGUUUAGAAUUUGAAUGUACAUCCAAAAUGAUGAGUUUCAAUUUAAGAGCCUUAAUAAAAUGUGUGAGUGUGUCUCAAUUGAA